CCAGUCCCGCUCCCUCCUCCUCUCCGUGCCUCUUUCUCCGCCCUGCUCCCCGCCAAACACACUUGCACAGGGGCUCUCAAGGUGUUCUCCGCACAGCGGAAGAUGGCGACAGACUGAGGGUGCAUGGCCAGCGGGAGCCACGGGGCCGUGCCGCUGGGCUGCAGCCACAGCGGUGCGAACGAGAGGCGGAAGCGAGAGGCGCACUAAGUAAAGCCCGGUGUCUGCGUCCGGCGCCUGUGGCGCUGCCGGGAGCCAGGUGGCCCGCCCGAGCCGGAACUCCAGGAGCAGCGGGUGCGGAGCCAGAGCGGAGCCCGCCAGGGACUGGCCCCGGCGAACACCCGGAGCGCGAACGAAGCCCGAAGGGCCCGGCAACGGACCGGCCGGCCGGCCUAGGAGGGCGCGAGCGAGGCAGGGAGCGGCGUGGAGCGGGCAGCGGGCGGACGGGCGGGAGCGGAGCGGCGCGGGGCGAGGGGAGCGGAGCGGAGCGCGGCGGCGGGGCCCGCACGGCGGCGCUGAGGGGCGCAGAGCUGCGCCGAACCGAGACGGCCGGUUUGGAGUGCGAGCCGGGCGGCCGCCGGCGCGGAGUGAAGUGGCACGGAGCCGAGGGCAGCUGAGGGGCCCGACACUAUGAGGAGUGCGGCGCCGCCGCCGCAGCCGCCACCGCCCCAGUGCCCCGCACCGCCCCCAGCCGGGACGCCGGGCAGCGCCUAGCGGGCCGGGCGGCGGCGCCCGGGCUGAGAGCGACGGAGCGCGGGAGCGGCGCGGAGACGGCACCAGAGCGCCCCGCGACUCCGGCCUGAGCGGGGCAUCGCGCCGGCCGGCCUGCCUCACCAUGCAGCCCCCGAGGUAGAGCCUGGACGGCGCCGAGGAGCGCAGAGCGGCGCGCAGCCCGCCCGCCCCAGACGGCCGUCUGGCCUCGCGCCUGCCUGUUCCCUCCAGCCCGGACCCCCCUGAAAUAUGUUCAGGGGCGCUUGGAUGUGGCCCGGGAAAGACGCCGCCGCGCUGACUAUCUGCUGCUGCUGCUGCUGCUGGGCUCCCAGGCCGAGCGACAAACCUUGCGCCGACUCCGAGCGGGCGCAGCGAUGGCGACUGUCCCUGGCGUCCCUGCUCUUCUUCACCGUGCUGCUCGCUGACCAUCUGUGGCUGUGCGCGGGGGCCCGGCCCCGGGCCAGGGAGCUGAGCAGCGCCAUGCGGCCCCCAUGGGGGGCCGGCCGGGAGCGGCAGCCGGUGCCUCCUCGCGCGGUGCUGCCGCUGCCGCCGCCGCCGCCCGGCGAGCCCAGCGCGCCCCCAGGCACCUGCGGCCCCAGAUACAGCAACCUGACCAAAGCCGCCCCCGCCGCCGGCUCUCGGCCGGUCUGCGGCGGCGUCCCAGAGCCCACGGGGCUGGACGCAGCUUGCACCAAAUUGCAAUCUUUGCAGAGACUUUUCGAACCGACUACUCCGGCCCCCCCUCUGCGGCCCCCUGACUCCCUUUCCCGUGCCCCGGCCGAGUUCCCCUCCGCCAAAAAAAACUUGCUCAAAGGCCACUUUCGGAACUUCACUCUCUCCUUUUGCGACACCUACACGGUCUGGGACUUGCUGCUGGGCAUGGACCGCCCCGACAGCCUGGACUGUAGCCUGGACACCCUGAUGGGGGACCUGCUGGCCGUGGUGGCCAGCCCGGGCUCCGGGGCCUGGGAGGCGUGUAGCAACUGUAUCGAGGCGUACCAGCGGCUGGACCGACACGCUCAGGAAAAAUAUGACGAGUUCGACCUCGUGCUGCAUAAAUACUUACAGGCGGAAGAGUACUCAAUCCGGUCCUGCACGAAAGGCUGUAAGAGGCUGGAACUGAACGUCCUGGGACUGGCUGGUGCAGGGGGAAGGCCAAAGAUGGGAGGAAGAAUAUUUGGCAACCAAACCCUCACCCUUUGGCUUCUGCCAGUGGGUGAGAGGACGAGCACUCCUGGUGGUGGGGCACACCACACACUUGACCUUAUGUGACCUGAGGUGACUGGCCAGAGCCGAGGCAGGUCGAGCCCAGGGGCUGCCUGUCUUCUCCCAAGGAAGUCACCUGCAGGCUCUUCUCCCCUGACAAAGGAAGGAGCUGGGAACAGGGAACAGCGACUGGUGGGAAGGCCACUGAAGGUUAGUGCAUUCUCAUACAAAACUCCCAGUGCCUUCCCAGCACCCCAUGGUGACAGUGGGGGGAACACUGGCUUUCUAGCUGCUGGGGAUAGGUAUCCAGAGGAGAGGUGAGGCAGCUGCAGACCGGCCCGCCUAGGGAAGAGCUGAGUGUUAAGAAACUUCUUGACCCUCGGCGGGGUUGCUCUGGACAGUUAGGUGGGUGAGGGCUGCAAACAUUUGGGACUUGAUGGUACUGCCCUGCUCGCCCAGCCUGGCCAGGUGACCUGCCUUUGGGAGGAAAGAGAACAGCAAGGUCAAAGGGUCAGAUGACAAGGAGACCAGGAGGGGUGGUGGCCUCACACAUCCUCGAGCUGGGGCCAAGAGCUGGAGAGUGAGACAGUUGCUUUCUAGCCUAGCUCGUGUCCCUCCAAGACUUUGGGGAGGGGCAGAAAGUGCCAUUUUCCAUCCAGCAUGGCCCUUGUGGACUUCUGCAGGGCUUCCAUGCUUUUAGCGGGUUCCCUAGGGAUUGGGGCAGAGGGUUGGGAAGGAAAAGGGUAGUUCCUCGCUCCUGACUUCACUUUCUCCUUCUCCUUUUUCCUGCUCUCGUAACCUAGCAGUCUCCCUCCCGCCUCCCUCAGCCUCAGCUGACUCACUGCCUCACUCACACUACCAAAUGAGAUAUUCCACUUCUUAAAGGUAUACAGACAGAUAGACACACACACUGCCAUACACCAUCACCACCACCCCGGGCAAAGUCACAUAGGCAUGCAGAGAGGUCGUCACACCCACAAACAGUGUCAUUAGAAGCAGAUGCCGUGUCACACACACGCACAUCUCCCCAUGGUAUCAGAGACACGCAGGCAGAAGUACUGUCACAUGAAGAAGGGCACAUUUUGUCUUACAGAGACACAUACCCUCGAUGUCAGCCACGGACACAUACACUCAGUGGGAGCAGAGAGACAGGGUCCACAAGCAGAUGGAAUCAAGGAUGUCUGUUUUUUGUGGCCCUCCCUUCAACCCCAUGGCCCUGUUUUUUGUUUGUUUGUUUUGUUUUUUUCCUCAAUCACCAGUAUGAAUGAGAGGCAUGCCACAACUUCCCCAUGGGGUUUUCUCCGUGUUGUAGUUGACUCCGAUUUCUGUCUGGACCUGAACUAAAUACAAAUCUCUCAUGUUGAUUGUUUUUACCAAGCAGUGUGACGUAGGAGAAAUACAUCUGAUCUCUCCAGUUCAGGAGGCCUUAUCACCUCUACUUCUUGUUAGUGGUAUGACCUUGGGCAAGUCACUUCACUUCUGUAAGCUUUCAUUUCCUCAUUUGUAAAACAGGGAUCAUCAUCCUUGCUCUGCCCACAUCCUGGGUCUUUUGUGGGAAGAAGGUGCAGAUGUAUUUUGUAAUAAGAAUAUAACAUCUGACAUUAAUGUAAUGCUUAAGGUUUUUCCGCCCCUCUCGUGUGUGUUAUGAGAUCAAGGAGGCUGGUGAUACUAGCACCACUACUCCCAUUUUACAGAUGAGGAAACUCAGGUGCAAGGGGAUCAAAUGGUUUGCCCUAAGGUCACUCAGCUAAUGAGCAGGAGUGCCAGGACUCCAGCCCACGUGUUUUGGUGCCAACCUCGUGCUUUUGCCAUGGCCUCACAUCAAGUUCCUGAUGGCCCUCCCUCCUCUCCUUUGUCUUCUUGUCUGUCUCUCUCCAGCAAACCAGCGAACUCCUCCUGUGCUCUCGCUGCCUGCUGUGCCGGCAGAAGGGCAGUGCCAGCUCCAUAGCUCUCUUCCGGCCUUUCCCACCCUUGUCCAAUGCUCUCUCCCUCAACUGAGGCCAGACCCACCUGGCUCUCGAAUCCAGCUGUAUGAUGGGCACGAAGGGAAAAGACAGCCCUGCUACCCUACUUGGACUGUAGGCUCCUCUCUCCUCAGUCCCUCACCCCACCUCCCUGGCAGGCCUUACUUGCCAUUCCCAAACCCCGUUCCUGGGCUCCAAGCCCUCCUGUCUGGUCCCCACCCCAAAUGGGAUCCCUGCGAGAUGACGCCCCACCCUCAGAGCUUCUCCUGAGUGGAGAGACCACAGCCCCAGGCCAAGAUGAAGAGGCUUUCUUACUUCUAGAAACCAAGCUGGGAACCUCUGUUUCAGAGCCAGGUGACCCCCUGUCCCCAGGACCCUGUACUGAGUGCAUCAGUUAGCUCUUCCCUGGGUGGCCCCAGAAACCCUGUUCUCUGCCUUUGCAAUAUCUGCCCCCGUUUCAGGCCACACAGGGCCCCACGAAUCAUACCUGUCCUCGCUGCUGCCUGUGACACCUCCCAAUUUAGUACCAGCUGCAACAUUUCCUUAAUGUGCAACUGACUUCCUCUCACACAGCAGGGCAAUGUAACUUAGGUAGGCCGAUGCCCUUCCCCGCCCUGGCCUCUCCCAACUCCCAGGGUCAUGCCUCACCUCUCUCUUAGCUUCCUGUGCAUCCCCACAAGCCCUAUUUCCUCCAACCCCCACCCCACUCUCUUGGCCAUAGCUAGGGUUACUGGACAACCACCACACUCCCCCAUGGCUCUCCAUCCUCCCAGUUCUGCCACACUCCUGCCUUUCUGAUUGCCUCUUCCCCCACCUCUGUCUCUUUCCUACUCUCUCUUCAGAACAUUCAGACUAGGGGGAGUGAUGGAGAUGGGGGCAAAAUCCUGGCUUCUUCUCUCAUAGCUGUUGAUCUGAGGGGAAAUAGAGGCCCAAGGGAGGGGCAGUUCUUAGCUCUCUCACCAGCCAUAGGGUUGCAUUAGUAAAGAUGAGUGCCAGGGAAGGAUGUGAUAGUUCUGCUCUAUUCCAGACUGACCCAAACCCACCUGGCAGACAGUGUGUUUGAUUUUGGGUCUCACACUGACUGGGCUGAGAAGGAGGCAGGAACCCAUGUUCUUCUGGAGAGAGUUGAAGGAGGUGUUUCACCUGGAGAAGAGGUGACUCGGGCAGAUAUGCUGUCUGACUUCACACCUCAGAAUAGUUGACAUGGUAUAAAUGAAAAAGCAUGACCUGCGUGGCCCCAAAGGGCUUUUAUAGUUAGAAAGUUCUAGGUUAAAACCUAGUUCUUUUAUUUAUUACCUGUGUAACCUUGAGCUAAGGACGUCAACUCUCUGAGCCUCACUUUUCUCACCUGUAAAAUGGGGCUAAUUCAUCGUAACAGUCCUGUGAGGUCAUUAUUAAUGAGAAGAGUCUUUACAGUACCCAGACCUGCCAUAUCAGAGUUGCUCAGUUUCUUCCUUUCAAAAAAGGAACAGACUGCCUUAGGAGGAAGUGAGCUCCUGCUCCCAGGAAGUGUCUGGCCCGAUACAGGUGGACCCUUGGGGAAAAUGCCGUGGAGGCAAUUCUAACACCAGAUUAUGAGCAGAGUUGGACCAGGUGACCUUUGAGGUAUAUUUCAGCCUGGAUUUUAGGCCUGUGAGCAAAGCUUGCUCAUUGAACAGCAGCACUGGAUGGGGAGGGCUGGGGAA